AGUGUCCCGGCCGCGCAGGACUUGACAUGCUGCCCGACUGCCUGUCGGCCGAGGGCGAGCUGCGCUGCCGCCGGCUGCUGGCAGGGGCCACGGCCCGGCUCCGCGCGCGGCCCGCGUCGGCCGCGGUGCUCGUGCCGCUCUGCUCAGUGCGUGGGGUCCCGGCGCUGCUGUACACGCUGCGGUCCAGCCGCCUGACCGGGAGGCACAAGGGCGACGUCAGUUUCCCAGGCGGCAAGUGCGACCCGGCUGACCAAGAUGUGGUGCACACGGCCCUGCGGGAAACCCGGGAGGAGCUGGGCCUGGCAGUGCCCGAGGAGCACGUGUGGGGCCUGCUGCGGCCUGUGUAUGAUCCGCAAAAGGCCACCGUGGUGCCAGUGCUUGCUGGUGUAGGCCCACUGGAUCCCCAGAGCCUCAGGCCCAACUCGGAGGAGGUGAGCUGGGGGAUAUGAGGGGGUUGGGCUGUUCCAGUCCUCUGUCUACCCUCUCUGCCUCCUGCCUGCAGGUAGAUGAGGUGUUUGCACUGCCGCUGGCCCACCUGCUGCAGACGCAGAAUCAGGGCUAUACCCACUUCUGCCGGGGUGGCCACUUCCGCUACACACUACCCGUCUUCCUGCAUGGACCACACCGGGUCUGGGGCCUCACAGCUGUCAUCACUGAGUUUGCCCUGCAGCUGCUGGCACCUGGUACCUACCAGCCCCGCCUGGCCGGCCUGACCUGCUCAGGGGCUGAGGGUCUGGCCCGCCCUAAGCAGCCCCUGGCUUCACCCUGUCAGGCCAGCUCCACUCCAGGACUGAAUAAAGGUCUUUGACAGCUCUA